ACUCUUUAGAUCUCUCUUGAAGAGGGCUGGUAUAUUUGUGCCUGCUGGAGGUGGAAUUAACAGUAAGAAGGAGAAAGGGAUUGAAUGGACUUACAGGAAGGAUUUCAAGUAAAUUCAGGGAAACACAUUUACUUGAAUAGUACAACCUAGAGUAUUAUUUUACACUAAGACGACACAAAAGAUGUUAAAGUUAUCACCAAGCUGCCGGACAGAUAUAUAUUCCAACACCAAGGUGCAGAUCAGCAUAGAUCUGUGAUUCAGAAAUCAGGAUUUGUUUUGGAAAGAGCUCAAGGGUUGAGAAGAACUCAAAAGCAAGUGAAGAUUACUUUGGGAACUACAGUUUAUCAGAAGAUCAACUUUUGCUAAUUCAAAUACCAAAGGCCUGAUUAUCAUAAAUUCAUAUAGGAAUGCAUAGGUCAUCUGAUCAAAUAAUAUUAGCCGUCUUCUGCUACAUCAAUGCAGCAAAAACUCUUAACAACUGUGGAUAAUUGGAAAUCUGAGUUUCAGCUUUCUUAGAAAUAACUACUCUUGACAUAUUCCAAAAUAUUUAAAAUAGGACAGGAAAAUCGGUGAGGAUGUUGUGCUCAGAAAUGUCACUGUCAUGAAAAAUAGGUAAAUUUGUUUUUUCAGCUACUGGGAAACUGUACCUCCUAGAACCUUAGGUUUUUUUUUUUUUUAAGAGGACAAGAAGGACUAAAAAUAUCAACUUUUGCUUUUGGACAAAAAUGCAUCUGACUGUAUUUUUACUUAAGGGUAUUGUGGGUUUCCUCUGGAGCUGCUGGGUUCUAGUGGGUUAUGCAAAAGGAGGUUUGGGAGACAAUCAUGUUCACUCCAGUUUUAUUUAUAGAAGACUACGGAACCACGAAAGACGGGAAAUACAAAGGGAAAUUCUCUCUAUCUUGGGUUUGCCUCACAGACCCAGACCAUUUUCACCUGGAAAACAAGCGUCCUCUGCACCUCUCUUUAUGCUGGAUCUCUACAAUGCCAUGACCAAUGAAGAAAAUCCUGAAGAGUCGGAGUACUCAGUAAGGGCAUCCUUGGCAGAAGAGACCAGAGGGGCAAGAAAGGGAUACCCAGCCUCUCCCAAUGGGUAUCCUCGUCGCAUACAGUUAUCUCGGACGACUCCUCUGACCACCCAGAGUCCUCCUCUAGCCAGCCUCCAUGAUACCAACUUUCUGAAUGAUGCUGACAUGGUCAUGAGCUUUGUCAACUUAGUUGAAAGAGACAAGGAUUUUUCUCACCAGCGAAGGCAUUACAAAGAAUUUCGAUUUGAUCUUACCCAAAUUCCUCAUGGAGAGGCAGUGACAGCAGCUGAAUUCCGGAUAUACAAGGACCGGAGCAACAACCGAUUUGAAAAUGAAACAAUUAAGAUUAGCAUAUAUCAAAUCAUCAAGGAAUACACAAAUAGGGAUGCAGAUCUGUUCUUGUUAGACACAAGAAAGGCCCAAGCUUUAGAUGUGGGUUGGCUUGUCUUUGAUAUCACUGUGACCAGCAAUCAUUGGGUGAUUAAUCCCCAGAAUAAUUUGGGCUUACAGCUCUGUGCAGAAACAGGGGAUGGACGCAGUAUCAACGUAAAAUCUGCUGGUCUUGUGGGAAGACAGGGACCUCAGUCAAAACAACCAUUCAUGGUGGCCUUCUUCAAGGCGAGUGAGGUACUUCUUCGAUCCGUGAGAGCAGCCAACAAACGAAAAAAUCAAAACCGCAAUAAAUCCAGCUCUCAUCAGGACUCCUCCAGAAUGUCCAGUGUUGGAGAGACGCUCCAUAAAACUACUAGGUGGAAUUCAUUGGACUUUUCCUAAAGGGUAGGCACCAGGAGAAUCACGUUAGAAGUCCUAUUUGUGUGGCAAGCAACAGAAGCAGGAGGGAAGAUUUCUGUAUGGAAUUGCAUUAUACUGAAUUAAAUGCUGCUUAUAAGGUGAUGUUUUAAAAUAAUUUUCCAACAAAGAAAUUUAACCACUUUUAGUAAAGCAUGACACUAGUGCCUUAUUACAACGCUAUUUUUUAAAGAUAUUCACAAGAUAUUUAGUUUGGCAAAAAGCUGUAAUUACUUAAUAUGAAAGAUGGAGAAAAAUAACUUUCUAAGACCUUUUCUUCCUGGUAAAUACUAGGCUGUCAAACUUGUAUAUUUUUCUUUUCAUGUAGAAUGGUUCUAAGUUUGGUUGAAAUGUUUUUAAUUUAAUGUAGCAGACUGUAUUAAGAAAAAGUUUUGCUAAACCUUGAAUAGAAUAGUAAAUAAUUUUGGAGGAAAUUACAAAGGGAAAAGUAUAAGUCACAUACUUAUUAUUUGAGCUCAUAAUGACUCUGGCAGAGGUGUUCCGGUGACUGAAAUCAUCAAAGUCCUUUUCCCUAUUGGUUAACUCUAUUUAUCUUCUCUUCCUAACCACAAGAAACAAAUGUACGUCUAUAAGCAGAGAUGAAUAAAACACAUGGAGCAGAAAUCACGUAACUUUUCACCAGUUUCCUAACACCAUUUAGAGUACAAAAUUAUUCUAAUAUAGACCAAUAUUUUCUUUUUGAAAUUUUGUCAUUGGCAACCAUUUCUGUGAAAUAUGUGGUAGAUGGUUUUGGAGUGUGUUCAUAUUUUGAUAAGAAGAAGAAAGAAAGUAGCUGGUUUGUGUCUAUAAGACUUAACCUUUCAAUAGGUAGUAAUCAAGCAGUCUGGGAAAAUCCUCAUAGGAUUUGGUCUAAAAGACAAGGCUUUAAGGAAAGGGAAUGCUAAUAUAAACAGAAAAUUUGAUACUUCAGAGACUUGAAAUGCCAGUGAAAUUUAAAAAUUAUCCAAAUAUAAAUAACAAAGUUGUAAUAGUAACUAGAUUUUACAAUAAGAUAUUGUGCAAAGGCUCUAUGGAUAAGAAGGGGUGGGAUGGGGAUGGAGUUAGGGAGGAAAGUUGUAUUGCCUGUUUGCCUGAUUGCUGGGUUUUUUGCAAAGCAUAUUAUCAAAUGUUGAAAAUCUCCAUUAGUACAGAAGAAUUAAAACCCAAGUCAUUUCUGCUAUCUUUAUCACAUUUCUUUUCUACUUCAACGAUUCUUCCUUCUGACUUCCUGAUGUUCUUUUUUUCUUCCAUAUUCCUGUGGGAGAGCUUAGAACAGAAACCAGCACAGAAUAGGAGUCCCCAAAAUACUUGUUGAGUAAAUUAACGUGCUGACAGCAUAGGAAAAACUAACUUCGUUUUUCAAGUAAAGGUAUAUAGAACCAUUACUUCCAGGUUUCCUGCAGAAACUGCCCGGCACUGCUUGUUCCUCUUCAGGUUUUUGGCAAGAUGGUUGAACAGACACAUUGUGGAAGAUAUUUCCUGUUUCAUGUUGAGGCAGUGCAAAGGGUAUUUCUUUGAAUUUGUGUAUGAGAGGAAAGAAAAUGGAGCCAAUAGCUAAAUUCUAAGCUAGCUAUCCUUGAAGAUAUAAAGGCACUAGGUGGAUAAGAUUUUUUUAAAAACCUCCAGAACAUGAUGCUGCUUGAAGGAGUAUAUUCAGUGUUGAAAAGAAUAGAGUACAGGCAUACCAUGUUUUAUUGCAUUUUGCUUUAUUGUGUUUCAAAGAUAAUGUGUUUUUUACAAACUGAAGUUUUGUGGCAGUCCUGCAUUAAGCAAGUCUAUUGGUGACAUUUUUUCCAACAGCAUUUGUUUACUUGGUUUCUCUGUGUCACAUUUUGGUAAUUUUUGCAAUAUUUCAAAAUUUUACUGUUAUUAUUAUAUUUGUUAUGGUUUAUGUUAUCAGUGAUCUUUGAUAUUUAUUGGUAAUUGUUUUGUGACACCACAAAUUUUACCCAUAUAAGAUGGGAAGUAAAUGUUGUGUGUGUUCUGAUUGCUCCAACGAUCGGUCAUUACCCCAUCUCUUUCCCUUCUCUUGGGUUCCCUAUUCCCUGAGACACAAUAUUGAAAUAAGUUCAGUUAGUACCCGACAAUGGCCUAAAAGUGUUCAAAUGAAAGGAAGAUUUAAACAUCUCUCACUUUAAAUCAAAAGCUAGUAAUGAUUACGCUUAUUGAGGAAGGUAUGUUGAAAGUCCAGAUAGAUUGAAAGCUAGGCCUCUUGUGCCAAACAAACAGUUGUCAAGUUGUGACUGCAAAGGAAAAGUACUUGAAGAAAAUUAUAAGUAUGACUUCAUCAACACAAUAAUGAUAAGAAAGCGAAAUCGUUUUCUUGCUGAUGUGGAGAACGUUUGAGUGGUCUGGAUGGAAGAUCAAACCAGCCACAACAUUCCUUUAUACCAAAGCCUUAUUCAGAGCAAAGCCCUGAUUCUCCUCAAUUCUAUGAAGGCUGAGAGAGCUGAGGAAGCUGCAGAAGAAAAGUCUGAAAGUAGCAGAUAUUGGUUCAUGACGUUUAAGGAAAGAAGCUGUCUCCAUAGCAAAAAAGUGCAAGGUGAAACAGCAAGUAUUGAUGAAGAAGCUAUAGCAAGUUAUCCAGGAGAUCUAUCUAAGAUCACUGAUGAAGGUAGCUACACUGAACCACAGAUUUUUAAUGGAGAUUAAGAAGCCUUAUUGGAAGAUGUUAUGUAGGACUUUCAUAGCUAGAGAAGAGUCAAUGGCUGGCUUCAAAUCUUCUGACAAUCUGACUCUCUUGUUAUGGGCUAAUAUACCUGGUGAGAUUAAAUUGAAGACAAUGCUCAUUUACCAUUCUGAAAAUCCUUGGACCCCUAAGUAUCAUGAUUAAUCUACUCUUCCUGGGCUCUGCAAAUGGAAGAACAAAACCUGGAUGAACAGUGCAUCUGUUGAUAGCAUGGUUUAUUAACUAUUUUAGGCAAACUGUUGAGACCUAUUGUCCAGAAAAAAGAUUCCUUUCAAAAUAUUAGUGCCCAUUGACAAUGUACUUGAUCACCCAAGAGCUCUGAUGGAGAUAUACGAGUAGACUAAUUGUUUUUAUCAUGCUUGCUAGCACAACAUCCAUUCUGCUGCCCAUGCAUGAAAGAGUAGUUUUGACUUCCAAGUUUUAUUAUUUUAAAGAUUUAUUUUGUAAUUCUACAGCUUCCAUAAAUAGUGAUUCCCCUGAAGGAUCUAGGCAACCUUCUGGAAAGGAUUCACCAUUCUAGAUUCCAUUUAAGAACACUCAUGAUUUAUGAGGGGUUGAAAUAUCAACAUUAACAAGGGUUUGGAAGAAGUUGAUUCCUACCUCCUGGAUGACUUUGAUGGGUUCAAGACUUCAGUGGAGGAAAUCAUUGCAGUUGUGGUAGAAAUAGCAAGAGAACUUGAAUUACAAGCGGAACCUGAAUAUAUGACUGGAUUGCUGCAAUCUCAUAAUAAAACUUGAAUGAAUGAGGAGUUGCUUCUUAUGGUUGAGCAAAAAAAGUGGUUUCUGGAUAUAAAAUCUUCCUGGUGAAGAUACUGUGAAUGCAAUUGUAAUGACAACAAAGGAUUUAGCAUUUUAAAUAAGUUUAUUUACUAGAGUAGAGGCAGGAUUUGAGAAGAUGGACUCCAAUUUUAAAAGAAGACCUUCACAAAGUAAAGUGCUAUCAAACAGCCUUGCACACUACACAAAGAAUCUUUUGUGAAAGGAAGAGUCAAUCAAUGUGACAAAUUUUAUCGUUGUCUUUUAAGAAAUUGCCACAGCCACAUCAACCUUCAGCAAUCACCAACCUGAUCAGUCAGCAGGUAUCAACAUUGAGGCAAGACCCUUUACUAGCAAAAGGAUUACAACUUGCUGAAGACUCAGAUGAUCACUAGCAUUUUUUAAUCAAUAGAUUAUUUUUAACUAAGGUAUGUACAUUUUUAAAGAUAUAAUCCAAUUACACACUUAAUUGACUGUAGUAUAAUGUAACCAUAACUUUUACAUGCACUGGGAAACCAAAAAAUAUUGUGACACUCACUUUAUUGUGACGUUCACUUCAUUGCAGUGGUCUGGAACUAAAUUCACAAUAUCUCCCCAGUAAAUGUCUCUGACAUAUGCCUGUAUGAAGAAUCCAAAAGAAUUAACAGGGCAAAUGGCAAGUCCUGGAUCAUUACAGAACUGCUAAGAAAGAUUGCUAUUGUAUGCUGGAUACUGAGAAUCUUCGAAAAAUAAUCCAAUCAUGUAGUGGCCCUGCCUACAUCCAUGGUGAUUUCGUAGGGCAAGUCUUUGGUAUACAGGUGCUCUUCAACUUAAAAUGGGGUUAUAUCCCAAUAAACCCAAAUAAAGUUUGCAGUACCAUAAGCUCAAAUAUCAUAGCUUAGCCUAGCCUCCCUUACACAUGCCCAUAACAUUUACAUUAGCCUACAGCUGGGCAAACUCAUCUAAAACAAGGCCUAUUUCAUAAUUAAGUUUUGAAUAUCUUAUGUAAUUUAUUGGACACUCUACUGAAAGUGAAAAACAGAAUGCUUGUGUGGGUACUCAUAGUAUGAUUUCUACUGAAUGUGUAUUGCUUUCAAACCAUCAUCAAUUUAAAAAAUCUUAAGUCAAAGCAUUGUAAAUCAGAUAAAAUGCAUAGUUACUAAAAUUGAAACAUUCUAUUCUUGUUCUCAAAUUUGAUAGGCGCUAUCUCUUGCCUAAUAAAUACAAUGUAAAUUUAUGCCUCUUGGAAAAACAGAUAUUAGUCAAAACAAGAAAAUAAUUAAUUGAAGUUAUUUCCAUCGAAUGUUUUAUAUUAUAUAAUUAAUACACUGUUUUAGUGUUUAGAAAUAAUAAAAUCAUAAAUAAAGCUAAAGUUCUCCCUUGUUUACCUAAUCCAUACAUAAUAGAUUACCUUAAUAUGCUGAUAUCAACAUGGUACAAACCUCUCUCUCAUCUCUUUUGAGAGAAUGUAUUUUUGUUAUAUGCUUUUAAUUACAUGAAUUAUAUAUUUUACAGGUUUUAUAAACAAUGUUUAGCCAUAUGUCAAAUAACGUGAGCUAAUUCUUUUCAACUGUUGCAGCUUAGUAUUGGCAUCAGUUUAUUUAAUCAUGUCACUCCAAAAAGACAUUUUGCUUUUUUUCCAAGUUGGCACUCUCAAAAUAAAUGCUGUACUGAAAAUCCUGCAAUGCUGCACAAGUGAGAAUAUUUCUAAUCCACGUAAUUAUGACAGUAACUAAUAUUAAAAGUUGCUAUCUGUGCCCUGAAUCAUGAAAAAUUCUGGAAACCCCUCCUGAAACAAGUAUGUUGAUGCAUAUAGUAUGUCGUUAGCUAGCUCUCUCUAUCUAUAUAUUUAUCUAUCAUCUAUCCAUCACUUAAUAUCUAAUACUGACUUCACUACUUACUAGUUGUAUAAUCUUGCACAAGAUAUAUUACCUCUCUCUGACUGUUUCCUCAUGUAUAAAGUGGGAAUGUUAAUUAUACCUGCCUUGCAGAGCAGGAUUACAAGAGUUCUGAGGAUUAAAUGAGUUAUUAUAUAUAACUAAUUUAAAAUAGUGGUACACGGCAAAUGCUCAUUAAGUGUUGAACAUUAUAAUUGGUUUUAUAGAACUGGUACAAAAGGAGUUCAAACUCUUACAUCAGAGAAAACCAGAAGUUCACACUCUCUCUUAUAAGUACUCAUACCUGUGGUCACAGGAUUUCUUAUCUUUUGAGACUUUAGAAGCAAGAGAAAUUUUAGUCUUUAACCUAAUUUGGCUAAUCUAUAUUAGCAAUUAACUACACACUUUAAAAAAGACUUGCCAAUAGACAUUAAGGCAUUGUGUCUGUUGUUAAAUUUCUCUCUAGGAAAAAUCCACAGGAAGAAUAUAUCUGGGUAUAAUUUCUUAUAAAUAAUAUUUAUUCAAUAUCAAAUAAACUCCCAUUAUAUGCCAGGCACAGCAUUAUAUGCUAUAUAACUAUAUGCCAUGCACUAUAUUAACUAUAUGGCCCAAAAUACUACAUGAGGGACUUAUCUGAGAAUAAAUAGACAUUUUCUAGAAUUAACAGACAUGGAUGAAACCAUUUCAGGUUGUAGAAAUGAAAUGGCUCUACAGUUGUAGAGCCAUGGACCAUUGUCAAAUGGCUGGGGUAUGCAUGUAUUUUUAUGUGAGAGGAAUGUGGUAUCAGCUAGGAAAUUAUUAAGGGGCCAAAUCAUAAAGAGUAGGGUAUGUGAUGAUAAGGAGCAGUGAUGUCUUCCCAUAGGCAAUUGGAAAAAGAAGAAUCAUAACCAGAUAUGCAUUUUAAAAAGUUAAUUUUGGCCAUGGAGUGCAGAAUGGAAUGCCAAGGGUGGAGACAGAAAACUCAAAUAAUGAUUAGGGUCUAGUAUAAUACUCCAAGCAAUGAAGAUCAUAGAUUGGAGAGAGAGAUGUAAGAACCAAAACACACUGGAUAAGGCCAGCAGGGGUUUGAAGAGGGUGGAUAACCCAGGACUCUGGAGAGGGGAGUGUUGAGAGUAAGUGGAAUGUGUAGGGAAAAGAUAUAGCUAUAAGCCAAAUUGUUAGAUGUAGGAUGAGGCUGACCAAAUGCCACAGGAAACAAA